GGUGAGGACAGCCUGCCAGAGUCUGGUCUCUGGACACUAUGGGCACACGACUCCUCCCAGCUCUGUUUCUUGUCCUCCUGGUAUUGGGAUUUGAGGUCCAGGGGACCCAACAGCCCCAGCAAGAUGAGAUGCCUAGCCCGACCUUCCUCACCCAGGUGAAGGAAUCUCUCUCCAGUUACUGGGAGUCAGCAAAGACAGCCGCCCAGAACCUGUACGAGAAGACAUACCUGCCCGCUGUAGAUGAGAAACUCAGGGACUUGUACAGCAAAAGCACAGCAGCCAUGAGCACUUACACAGGCAUUUUUACUGACCAAGUUCUUUCUGUGCUGAAGGGAGAGGAGUAACAGCCAGACCCCCCAUCAGUGGACAAGGGGAGAGUCCCCUACUCCCCUGAUCCCCCAGGUUCAGACUGAGCUCCCCCUUCCCAGUAGCUCUUGCAUCCUCCUCCCAACUCUAGCCUGAAUUCUUUUCAAUAAAAAAUACAAUUCAAGUUGCUUCUCAUGGAUGGCACUGCUUUUCUGAGGACUCAAGGGCCAAGAUGGAGGGGCUGACUCAGUCCAGCCAACAUUUAAUGAGCACCUACUUUAUGUAUGGAGCUCUAACCCAUGGGUCCAUGGGAAUAAAGCAGUGAAUAGUAACAAUAAAUAAUCGUAACAGCAA